GUUGACGCAGCAGCGGCGGCGGUGGCGGCGGAGGGGCCGUGCGGUGGGUCCGUACUAUCUUUUCCCAGUCUCGGUUCGACGACUCCAUUUUCCUCGGUGGGGGCUUAGCGCACUGGAGGAGCGGCGGGCUUCAGACAGGCGAUGGGAAGAAAGAGAACACAGCUAUCUUUCCAAGCUGUGUGCAGCAUGGAGCACCAGCUGCCCUUGAGACAGAAGAAAGCUGUUGUUUUCAUCAGGGUCUUUACAGUCACUCCUCAACUUUUUGGACUCAGGACCCCUUUAUACUCUUAAAACUUAUUUAGGACUUCAAAGACAUUUUGUUUAUGUGAGUUAUAUCCUUUGAUAUUUACCAGAUUCGAAAUUAAAACUCAGUGAGACAUUUAAAAAUAUUUAUUGAUUUAUUUUAAAGUAGUAAACAAUAAUACUUUUUAUGAAUAACAGUAGUUUUUUGGGUUUUUUUGUUUGUUUGUUUGUUUUGAGACGGAGUCUCACUGUCGGUGCAGUAGCACCAUCUUGGCUCACUGCAACCUCUGCCUUCCAGGUUCAAGCAAUUCUCCUGCUUCAGCCUCCUGAAUAGCUGGGACUACAGGCGCCUGCCACCAUACCCAGCUAAUUUUUCAUUUUUAGUGGAGGCAGAGUUUCACCAUGUUGGCCAGGCUGGUCUCAAACUGCUGACCUCAGGUGAUCGGCCUGCCUCGGCCUGGGGUUACAGGCAUGAGCCACAGCACUCGGCCGAAUAAUAAUAGUUUUUAAAACAAAACAUUUUAGUAAGAAUGGACUGGGUGUGGUGGCUCACUCCUGUAAUCCCAGAACUUUGGAAGGUCGAGGCAGGUGGAUCACUUGAGCUCAGGAGUUCGAAACCAGCCUGGCUAACAUGGUGAAACUUUGUCUUAAAAAAUAAAUGAAUAGCCGGGCGUGGUGGCUCACGCCUGUAGUCCCAGCACUUUGGGAGGCCAAGGCAGGUGGAUCACUUGAGGUCAGGAGUUCGAGACCAGCCUGGCCAAUAUGGCCAAACCCCAUCUCUACUAAAAAAAACAAAAAUUAGCUAGACGUGGUGGCGAGCGCCUGUAGUCCCACCUACUCGGGAGGCUGAGGCAAGAGAAUCGCUUGAACCCAGGAGGCGGAGGUUGCAGCGAGCCAGGAUCGUGCCAUUGCACUUCAUCCUGGGUGAGAGAGUAAGACUCUGUCUCAAAAUAAGUAAAUUAAGUAAGAAUGACAUUCUUUGUUUUUUAGUACAAUGUUUUAAUGUCUGCUCUAACAGAAUACAGCUGUGUUCUCAUAUGUUUUUGCAUUCAGUCUGUUGUGAUAACCACAUGUCCUAUAACCUCUGGAAAACUCCACUCUAUGCUCCUGAGAGAACAGAGGGACUGGCCCCUGGACCACGCCCUGAAAACUAUUGAUAGAUGUGGUACUGUCAACCAUGAAGAGUCAGACAGACCUCAGCACUUACAGAUGAUAGUUUUGUCACCUUGAACAAAUGACUACAUCUCUCUGAGUCUGUUUCCUCCUCUGUUGAGAGAGAAGUGUGCUGUAACUCAUAGGACAGUGUAGGGAUUAAUAGAAUACUUGUUCUCCUUGAUAGGGACAUAAAAUAGUAGGGUAUUUGUUAGUGUCUGGCACUUGGUAGGUGUGUAAUAAGCAUUAUUCCUCAGGGUACUUUUUAAAAAAUUGCUUAAAAUACCCAAGAGAGACCCAUAUUAUUUUGAUUGGGUUUUGUGUGUGUGUUGUGAGUUUAUUGUCCAGUUCUCUUCCUGUGCCUGUUCUGUGUGUCUAUUGUAAUAUAUAAAACGAUUUUAUGGUCCUUAUUUUCAUAUUUCUAUCUCUAGGAGACAUUCAACUCCUUGAAAAUGAACAAUCCGGCCAGGCGCGGUGGCUCACGCCUGUAAAUCCCAGCACUUUGGGAGGCCGAGGCGGGCAGAUCACCUGAGGUCAGGAGUUCAAGACCAGCCUGACCAACAUGGAGAAACCCCCUCUCUACUAAAAAUGCAAAAUUAGCCAGCAUGGUGGUGCAUGCCUGUAAUCCCAGCUACUCGGGAGGCUGAGGCAGGAGAAUCGCUUGAACCCAGGAGGUGGAGGUUGCGGUGAGCCGAGAUCACGCCAUUGCACUCCAGCCUGGGCAACAAGAGCGAAACUCCAUCUCAAAAAAAAAAAAGAAAGAAAAUGAACAAUUCUCUUCAAAUCCCCAGCUCUUAGCAGAGUAUAUGUACAUUGUAGGCAUUCAGUUAGGUUUGUGGAAAGAAUGGCAUCUGAAACCUCAACCGAAAAUUGAACAUUCCCCCUCCCUCCUAUACCUUCAGUUUUGUUUUCUUGAGUUUAGUUAAUCUCAAGUUCAUUGGUUAUAGUAUUGAUUGAGCUCCGUAAGGGCAAUUUUGAGGAGAAUUAGAGCCACAGAACUUAAGGCACCUUCAGGUAGCCAUUAGCCACCCUUCUCUUCUCUCCCCUCCCACUGCCAUCUUUAACUGGGAAGAUGGCAGCAAUAUGAAAACUUAUCUUCAGGCAGAGUGAGAAGCUGCAGCAAUGUCUGAUUUUGUGGAAAGCGAGGCUGAGGAGUCAGAGGAAGAAUACAAUGAUGAAGGCGAGGUGGUACCCCGAGUCACCAAGAAAUUUGUGGAAGAGGAGGAUGAUGAUGAGGAGGAGGAGGAGGAGAACCUAGAUGAUCAGGAUGAGCAAGGCAACUUGAAAGGCUUUAUCAAUGACGAUGAUGAUGAAGAUGAAGGGGAGGAGGAUGAGGGCAGUGACUCUGGUGAUUCAGAAGAUGAUGUUGGCCACAAGAAGAGAAAACGCACCUCUUUUGAUGACCGCCUGGAGGAUGAUGAUUUUGACCUCAUUGAGGAGAAUUUGGGUGUCAAAGUCAAAAGAGGACAAAAGUACCGGCGUGUCAAAAAAAUGUCAGAUGACGAGGACGAUGACGAGGAGGAAUAUGGCAAGGAGGAACAUGAAAAAGAAGCUAUUGCGGAAGAAAUCUUCCAGGAUGGGGAAGGGGAAGAAGGGCAGGAGGCCAUGGAGGCCCCCAUGGCUCCUCCAGAGGAGGAGGAAGAAGAUGAUGAGGAGUCAGAUAUUGACGACUUCAUUGUGGAUGAUGAUGGACAGCCUCUGAAAAAACCUAAGUGGCGGAAAAAGCUUCCUGGAUACACAGACGCGGCCCUGCAAGAAGCCCAGGAAAUCUUCGGUGUGGACUUUGACUAUGAUGAAUUUGAGAAAUACAAUGAGUAUGAUGAAGAACUGGAGGAAGAGUAUGAGUAUGAGGAUGAUGAGGCUGAGGGUGAAAUCCGAGUGCGCCCCAAGAAGACCACCAAGAAGCGUGUGAGCCGUAGGAGCAUCUUUGAAAUGUAUGAGCCCAGUGAGCUAGAAAGCAGCCACCUCACAGAUCAGGACAAUGAAAUCCGAGCCACUGACCUGCCUGAGAGGUUCCAGCUCCGCUCCAUCCCAGUCAAGGGGGCUGAAGAUGAUGAACUAGAAGAAGAAGCUGACUGGAUCUACAGGAAUGCUUUUGCCACACCAACCAUUUCUCUCCAGGAAAGCUGUGAUUACCUAGACCGAGGGCAGCCAGCCAGCAGCUUCAGUCGGAAAGGGCCCAGCACAAUUCAGAAGAUCAAAGAGGCCCUGGGCUUCAUGCGAAAUCAGCAUUUUGAGGUGCCUUUUAUUGCCUUCUAUCGAAAGGAGUAUGUGGAGCCUGAGUUGCACAUCAAUGACCUAUGGAGAGUCUGGCAGUGGGAUGAAAAGUGGACCCAGCUGCGGAUCCGUAAAGAGAACCUAACACGGCUGUUUGAGAAGAUGCAGGCUUAUCAGUAUGAACAGAUCUCUGCUGACCCUGACAAACCUCUUGCUGAUGGCAUCCGGGCUCUGGACACCACUGACAUGGAGAGGCUCAAGGAUGUCCAAUCAAUGGAUGAGCUGAAAGAUGUCUACAACCAUUUUCUUCUUUAUUAUGGCCGAGACAUCCCUAAGAUGCAGAACGCCGCCAAAGCUAGCCGCAAGAAGCUGAAGCGUGUCAGGGAAGAGGGAGAUGAAGAAGGUGAAGGUGACGAGGCAGAAGAUGAGGAGCAGAGGGGGCCUGAGCUCAAGCAAGCCUCUCGCCGAGACAUGUACACCAUCUGCCAGAGUGCUGGGCUAGAUGGCCUGGCCAAAAAGUUUGGGCUUACUCCCGAGCAGUUUGGGGAGAACCUGCGGGAUAGCUACCAGCGGCACGAGACAGAGCAGUUUCCCGCGGAGCCCUUGGAGCUGGCCAAGGAUUACGUUUGCAGCCAGUUCCCUACUCCAGAAGCUGUGCUAGAAGGCGCCCGCUACAUGGUAGCCCUGCAGAUUGCCCGUGAGCCCCUUGUCCGGCAGGUGCUGAGGCAAACCUUCCAAGAGAGAGCCAAGUUAAAUAUAACCCCCACCAAGAAAGGUAGAAAGGAUGUGGAUGAGGCCCACUAUGCCUAUUCCUUCAAGUAUUUAAAGAACAAGCCUGUUAAGGAACUGAGAGAUGACCAGUUUCUCAAGAUAUGCCUGGCUGAAGACGAAGGGCUCCUCACCACUGACAUCAGCAUAGAUUUGAAGGGAGUGGAAGGCUAUGGCAACGACCAGACAUAUUUUGAGGAGAUAAAACAGUUUUACUACCGAGAUGAGUUCAGCCACCAGGUGCAGGAGUGGAACCGGCAGCGCACCAUGGCCAUCGAACGGGCUUUACAGCAGUUCCUCUAUGUGCAGAUGGCCAAAGAACUCAAGAACAAGCUGCUGGCUGAAGCCAAGGAAUAUGUCAUAAAGGCCUGUAGUCGAAAGCUCUACAAUUGGUUGAGAGUGGCACCCUACCGACCAGAUCAGCAGGUGGAAGAAGAUGACGACUUUAUGGACGAGAACCAAGGGAAGGGCAUUCGAGUCCUCGGCAUUGCUUUCUCCUCUGCCAGAGAUCACCCUGUGUUCUGCGCCCUGGUCAAUGGUGAAGGAGAAGUGACAGACUUCCUUCGACUGCCCCAUUUUACCAAACGGCGAACUGCAUGGAGAGAGGAAGAGCGGGAAAAGAAGGCUCAAGACAUUGAAACGCUAAAGAAAUUUCUCCUGAAUAAGAAGCCUCAUGUAGUGACAGUUGCAGGAGAGAACAGGGACGCCCAGAUGUUGAUUGAAGAUGUGAAGCGCAUUGUACAUGAGCUGGACCAGGGCCAGCAGCUGUCAUCUAUUGGGGUAGAGCUGGUUGACAACGAGUUGGCCAUUCUCUAUAUGAACAGCAAGAAGUCAGAGGCAGAGUUCCGGGAUUAUCCUCCAGUGCUGAGACAGGCCGUCUCCCUGGCCCGGCGCAUCCAGGACCCUCUGAUUGAAUUUGCCCAGGUGUGCAGUUCCGAUGAAGACAUCCUGUGUCUCAAGUUUCACCCCUUGCAGGAGCAUGUGGUGAAAGAGGAGCUGCUCAACGCCUUGUACUGUGAAUUUAUCAACCGAGUCAAUGAGGUCGGGGUCGAUGUCAACCGUGCCAUUGCCCACCCUUACAGCCAGGCCUUGAUCCAGUAUGUUUGUGGCCUGGGACCUCGGAAAGGGACCCACCUCCUGAAGAUCCUGAAGCAGAACAACACCCGGCUCGAGAGCCGGACCCAGCUGGUCACCAUGUGCCACAUGGGUCCCAAAGUCUUCAUGAAUUGUGCUGGCUUCCUCAAGAUCGACACGGCCUCCCUGGGGGACAGCACUGACUCAUAUAUUGAAGUCCUUGAUGGUUCCCGUGUCCACCCUGAGACUUAUGAGUGGGCUAGGAAGAUGGCAGUGGAUGCCCUGGAAUACGAUGAAUCAGCCGAGGAUGCCAAUCCUGCAGGAGCCCUUGAAGAAAUCUUGGAAAACCCAGAGCGACUGAAAGACCUGGACCUUGAUGCCUUUGCAGAAGAGCUGGAGAGGCAGGGCUAUGGUGACAAACACAUCACACUCUAUGACAUCCGGGCAGAGCUGAGCUGUCGAUAUAAGGACCUCCGGACAGCCUACCGCUCUCCCAACACAGAGGAGAUCUUCAAUAUGUUAACCAAAGAAACACCAGAGACCUUCUACAUUGGAAAGCUCAUCAUCUGCAAUGUCACUGGCAUUGCCCACAGGCGUCCCCAGGGUGAGAGCUAUGACCAGGCGAUCCGCAAUGAUGAGACAGGGCUGUGGCAGUGCCCCUUCUGUCAGCAGGACAAUUUCCCUGAACUAAGCGAGGUGUGGAACCACUUUGACAGCGGUUCGUGCCCAGGCCAGGCCAUCGGUGUCAAAACACGGCUAGACAAUGGUGUCACCGGCUUCAUCCCCACCAAAUUCCUCAGUGACAAAGUGGUAAAGCGGCCAGAAGAACGAGUGAAGGUGGGAAUGACUGUUCACUGCCGCAUCAUGAAGAUUGACAUUGAGAAGUUCAGUGCAGACCUGACCUGCCGCACCUCAGACCUCAUGGACAGGAACAAUGAGUGGAAGCUGCCCAAAGACACCUACUAUGACUUUGAUGCUGAAGCUGCAGACCACAAGCAGGAGGAGGACAUGAAGCGGAAGCAGCAGCGGACCACAUACAUCAAGAGAGUGAUCGCACACCCAUCCUUCCAUAAUAUCAAUUUCAAGCAAGCAGAAAAGAUGAUGGAGACCAUGGACCAGGGUGAUGUGAUUAUCCGACCAAGCAGCAAGGGCGAGAACCACCUGACAGUGACCUGGAAAGUCAGUGAUGGCAUCUACCAGCAUGUGGAUGUGCGGGAGGAGGGCAAGGAAAAUGCCUUCAGCCUGGGAGCCACUCUGUGGAUCAACAGUGAGGAAUUCGAAGAUUUGGAUGAGAUUGUUGCUCGCUAUGUCCAGCCCAUGGCAUCCUUUGCCCGGGACCUUCUGAAUCACAAGUAUUAUCAGGACUGCAGCGGUGGGGACCGCAAGAAAUUAGAGGAGCUGCUCAUCAAAACUAAGAAGGAGAAGCCCACCUUCAUCCCUUAUUUCAUCUGUGCCUGCAAGGAACUGCCCGGCAAGUUCCUACUGGGAUACCAGCCCCGGGGUAAACCCAGGAUAGAAUAUGUAACGGUGACUCCAGAGGGAUUCCGGUACCGGGGCCAGAUCUUCCCAACCGUGAAUGGACUGUUUAGAUGGUUUAAGGAUCACUACCAGGAUCCUGUACCAGGCAUCACCCCUAGCAGCAGCAGCAGGACCCGGACACCUGCCUCUAUCAAUGCUACCCCAGCCAACAUCAACCUUGCAGAUCUGACACGGGCUGUGAAUGCCCUGCCUCAGAACAUGACUUCACAGAUGUUCAGUGCCAUUGCUGCGGUGACAGGCCAAGGACAGAACCCUAAUGCCACCCCAGCCCAGUGGGCCUCCAGCCAGUACGGCUAUGGCGGCAGUGGAGGCGGCAGCAGUGCUUACCACGUAUUCCCAACGCCAGCCCAGCAGCCAGUGGCCACACCACUAAUGACCCCUAGCUACUCCUACACGACCCCAAGCCAGCCCAUCACCACCCCUCAGUACCACCAGCUCCAGGCCAGCACCACCCCACAGUCGGCCCAGGCCCAGCCCCAGCCCUCUUCCAGCUCCCGGCAACGGCAGCAGCAGCCAAAGUCCAACAGCCAUGCAGCCAUCGACUGGGGAAAAAUGGCGGAGCAGUGGCUGCAGGAAAAGGAGGCAGAACGGCGGAAACAGAAGCAGCGGCUGACACCUCGGCCCUCCCCCAGCCCCAUGAUCGAAAGCACCCCCAUGUCCAUUGCUGGCGAUGCCACCCCACUCCUGGACGAGAUGGAUCGGUAGGGGGCCUGCUCCUCGGACUCUGGUUACCUCUGAGGCUGGGAAAGGCCUGGCUGCCCACUGCCUCCCUCCCUGCCCCUCCUUUUAUGUCCAUAAAGUGGCGUGAAGUGAGACGUUCUCUUUGGUGGUCAACCCGGAUGGGUGACAGGCUGGAUGGCCUUGUGAACUUGAGCUCAGUGUAUGCUAGGCAACAAUUCUCCCGCUCCAGACCCUCACCGACCACCUGUCCUGGGACCAGGCUGGGAGGGGAGUGUGGCAGGGAGGAGGAAGAGGAAGGUGAGAAUGAGUAGAACAGUUUUGUAUUCUACUCCCUACAAGCCAUUUUGAACUUCUGCCCUCACCGGACUCUGGGCUGUGACUGGGGCACCAAACUCAGCACAUGAGUCUCCCCUAGCUCUCGUGGGGAGAGGGAUGCUAUUUAUUCAGUUUGGGGCAGGAGGGAGAGGAGGGAAAGUAUUUCUGACCCUGAUGCCAACAGCCGGGUGGCUGUCCAAGCAGGAUUGCAGGGGACACAGGGAAGCACUGCCCAGCCCCUGCCUGGCUGCCCUUUCCCCCCUGCUGCUGCCACCGCUUCCUGCCUGUCAUUUGAAUAAACAGUGUUUCUAUUGAGCUCUUGCCAAAGCCUCUCUCUCCAACUCUCCAGCUCUUUGAGGGGUGGCUUUCAAAGCAGUGUUUGGAGCUCCAAGGACUCCCCUGACUCCCUCUUCUGAUCCAUCAGAGGCAAAGAUUCAUAGACUAGAGGCAGCUUCUACAUCAGACUGCCUGGGGCACAUCCCUGCUCUACUUCCCAGCCGGGUGACCCUGUGCCAGUUCCUGCUGCCUUUCAGCUGGCUUUCUUACCUGUAACAUGGAGAUAGUGAUACCUGCCUCAUCAGCUGCUGUGAGGACCAAGGCAGCGUGUGCAAGCUCCUUGGCCCAACGCCUGGUACGUCGCAAAUGUUACCCGGUAUUAUUACACCCACUCACUCACCCACAGCACAGCUGCCCCAUCCGCCCAUGCCUGCUGGUCUUCUCUGGCACCCUGGAGAAAGGCCACAAGUAAAUCUGGAUUUCUCAA